ACUGCAACAGCGACUUCUCAGGCACCACCAGCAGCGCCACCGAGAGUUAUUAUUAUUUUUUGACCAAGCAGCACAUUUCCUGGUUCAGUGGCUUGAGCUCUGUGAGCAGCUGACUAGUCACCCCGGGUCUGGCUCAGGAUCAGCUGGUGACGCUGGGCUGGAGUCUAUGACUUCUUCCUUCAGAUUGUCAUGAAGAAGGGGAGUUAAGAGGAAACUGGGGGUCCUCCGGAAGGCGAUCUGAGCACUCAGGCUGAUCUAGAGGAAGAGUAGAAGUCAUACUUUUUUUCUCUUGCUUGGUGAAUUCCCCAGCAGAGUCUGGAUCCAGCAGUGCUGUUUUCCCUGAGGGAAUGUGGAGCAGCUCGGCUUGAGUCUGUUGCCAGCUUCAGGAAGGGUUCAGACUGAAAAGGGGGUUUGAGGAGAAGAUGCUUUGGCUGCCUGAGGUCCUGCUUGCGUUCUUAGAAGUCAGAUCCAGGGAGAAAGUGAACUGGGACAAUUGACAAGCUCCAAGGGUCUGGCAGAAGCUUCCUCCGAGACUGGGCAUUUCAUCCUCCCUGGAGGAAGAUCUGCCUGCACUGCAAGUGUCCCCAGGAGGAGCACAUGGUGACAGUGAUGCCGCUGGAGAUGGAGAAGACCAUCAGCAAACUCAUGUUUGACUUUCAGAGGAACUCGACCUCAGAUGAUGACUCAGGCUGUGCUUUGGAAGAGUAUGCCUGGGUCCCGCCGGGUCUGAAGCCUGAACAGGUACACCAGUACUAUAGCUGUCUCCCAGAAGAGAAAGUCCCUUAUGUCAACAGUCCUGGAGAGAAACUGCGAAUCAAGCAGCUACUACACCAGCUGCCGCCACAUGACAAUGAGGUUCGAUAUUGCAACUCCCUGGAUGAGGAAGAGAAGAGGGAGCUGAAGCUUUUCAGCAGCCAGAGGAAACGCGAAAACUUGGGCCGCGGGAAUGUCAGGCCUUUCCCAGUCACCAUGACAGGAGCUAUUUGUGAACAGUGCGGAGGCCAGAUCAAUGGUGGAGACAUCGCUGUGUUUGCGUCACGCGCUGGCCACGGCGUUUGCUGGCACCCGCCGUGCUUCGUAUGCACUGUCUGCAAUGAGCUCCUGGUGGAUCUGAUCUACUUUUACCAAGAUGGGAAGAUAUACUGUGGCAGGCACCAUGCUGAGUGCCUGAAGCCGCGCUGUGCUGCCUGCGAUGAGAUCAUCUUUGCAGAUGAAUGCACAGAAGCUGAGGGGCGACACUGGCACAUGAAACACUUUUGCUGCUUCGAGUGUGAGACAGUGCUGGGCGGCCAGCGCUACAUCAUGAAGGAGGGAAGACCCUACUGUUGCCACUGCUUCGAGUCCUUGUAUGCAGAAUAUUGUGACACCUGUGCCCAACAUAUAGGUAUCGACCAAGGUCAAAUGACCUAUGAUGGCCAACACUGGCAUGCCACUGAGACCUGUUUCUGCUGUGCUCACUGCAAGAAAUCCCUCCUGGGGCGGCCAUUCCUCCCGAAGCAGGGCCAGAUAUUCUGCUCACGGGCCUGCAGUGCUGGGGAAGACCCCAAUGGUUCUGACUCCUCUGAUUCCGCCUUCCAGAACGCCAGGGCCAAGGAGUCCCGGCGCAGUGCCAAAAUUGGCAAGAACAAGGGCAAGACGGAGGAGCCCAUGCUGAACCAGCACAGCCAGCUGCAAGUGAGUUCUAACCGGCUGUCAGCCGACGUAGACCCCCUGUCACUGCAGAUGGACAUGCUCAGCCUGUCCAGCCAGACACCCAGCCUCAACCGGGACCCCAUCUGGAGGAGCCGGGAAGAGCCCUACCAUUAUGGGAACAAGAUGGAGCAGAACCAGACCCAGAGCCCUCUGCAGCUCCUCAGCCAGUGCAACAUCAGAACUUCCUACAGUCCAGGAGGGCAAGGGGCUGGGGCCCAGCCCGAAAUGUGGGGCAAGCACUUCAGCAACCCCAAAAGGAGCUCGUCACUGGCCAUGACAGGACAUGCUGGCAGCUUCAUCAAGGAAUGCCGAGAAGACUAUUACCCGGGGAGGCUGAGAUCUCAGGAGAGCUACAGUGAUAUGUCUAGUCAGAGUUUCAGUGAGACCCGAGGCAGCAUCCAAGUCCCCAAAUAUGAGGAGGAAGAGGAAGAGGAAGGGGGCUUGUCCACUCAGCAGUGUCGGACCCGUCAUCCCAUCAGUUCCCUGAAAUACACAGAGGACAUGACGCCCACAGAGCAGACCCCUCGGGGCUCCAUGGAAUCCCUGGCCCUGUCUAAUGCAACAGGCCUCUCUGCUGAUGGUGGUGCCAAGCGCCAGGAGCACCUAUCCCGAUUUUCCAUGCCUGACCUCAGCAAAGACUCUGGAAUGAAUGUGUCUGAGAAGCUGAGCAACAUGGGCACUCUUAACUCGUCCAUGCAGUUCCGGAGCGCAGAGUCAGUUCGCAGCCUGCUCUCUGCCCAGCAGUACCAGGAGAUGGAGGGAAACCUCCACCAGCUCAGCAACCCCAUUGGCUACAGAGACCUGCAGUCCCACGGAAGGAUGCAUCAGAGCUUUGAUUUUGAUGGAGGGAUGGCGGGCAGCAAGCUGCCAGGGCAGGAGGGCGUGAGGAUCCAGCCCAUGAGUGAACGCACCCGGAGAAGAGCUACUUCACGCGACGACAACCGCCGUUUCCGACCUCACAGGUCCAGGCGUUCCCGACGCUCUCGCUCCGACAACGCCCUCCACCUGGCCAGCGAACGCGAGGCCAUCUCCCGGUUAAAAGAUAGGCCCCCUCUGAGAGCCAGGGAGGACUAUGACCAAUUUAUGCGCCAGCGGAGCUUCCAGGAGAGCAUGGGGCAUGGGUCCCGGAGGGACCUGUACGGCCAGUGCCCUAGGACUGUGUCGGACCUGGCUUUGCAGAAUGCCUUUGGGGACCGCUGGGGACCCUACUUCGCCGAGUAUGAUUGGUGUUCCACCUGCUCCUCCUCUUCAGAGUCUGACAACGAGGGCUAUUUCCUAGGAGAACCCAUCCCCCAGCCAGCGCGCCUGCGAUACGUCACAAGCGAUGAGCUGCUGCACAAAUACAGCUCCUACGGCCUCCCCAAAUCUUCCACAUUAGGUGGCAGAGGACAGUUGCACAGCAGGAAAAGACAGAAGAGCAAAAACUGUAUCAUUUCUUAAUAUGAUUGGGAUCAGGGAAUGGGAGAAGAUGGGAGCUAAGAAUGUAAAGUCAGAAACUUGCACUGUUUUAAAUGUUAAAGCGCUUUUGGGGGUGGCUUAUGGGGGAGAAAAGGGAAAAUGCUGUCAGUAGAUGGAGGCAAGGUUACAGGUUGACUCAAUAGGUAGUCACAGUUCUUGGCAUGUUGAAUAUUAUUUGCACAUUUCACUUUGGAAACACAGUAGACUCUAUCGAGGCCAGGCUUGGUCACUUCCUUCCCAUCAGUUCUGUGUUGAGUUGCCAUCUCUCAAGAUGGUAAAUUGUUUCCUGCUCGCUUUUAUCCUCUCUGGUUCUCUUACUUUUAGGACCCUUUUUUCAGUAAGUAAUUUGUUUAUUAGCCAGGACCCAAGACUAAGUUAUUUACAUGUCCAUUGUAAAUGCAAUGUAAAUGAGAGUUCUGAUAAAAUAUUUUUGUAUUUUGUAAUAUCAAAGGAAUUUCUAUAUCGUAGGACUCAGUGGGGACUUGCAUGCACAUCCACCAUUGUCUCUGAGUAGUAUUGAAAUGUGGCCCGGUACCACCUUUUUUUUUUUUUUUUUUUUUUCUAUACAAAUUUGUUACAUGUCAGUGAGACCUUUUUCAAAGGAACAUAUUCAAUUUGGCUUUUUGUGGCUGAAAAAACAUAACUGUUAGACCCAAAGCAUUUUAUGCUCCGUUCCAUCUUAAGGAGCCAUCCUUAAGUCUGCUCCCACCCUCAGUAGAAUUUAUUUUCUACAAAGUGGUAGUAAUUUUUUUUUAAAUUGCAAAUGUAAUUUUUGCCAAUUAGAGAAACCAACCGGUGUCAGUAAAAUUCUGUGAGAAAUGCCAUCCCUGCUGGGAAUGUUGAAGUUACUUAAUGUUGAUCUAUCCCUUGGGGAAAGUAAAAGUGACUGUGAGUGGUGCCAUUGUGUGAUGUCAGCAUGACGUUGUUUUGAAUGUGGCAUUAUGUUCUGGUGCUCAUGUUUCCUGGAUUGUAUUAUCUGCUUUCCUUUACCAAGGCAGACAGAACUGCUGCCUUAGCCUGACAACCGGUUGUCCUCAAAGCAAAUGAACUUAAGCAUUUGGGAUUGAGGGACAGAAGGAUUCUGAGGGGGCUCUGCGAGGGACGGUGUGUGACAUGUCAUGCCUGGAGAAGGAACAAGGCUAUUUGAAAACAGAAGGCAGGUCAAGGGUAGAAGUUAAAGGAGAAUCUGAAGGCAGGUCAGGGAAAAGAAGAACUGGAAAUGAAACAGAGGACAGGUGACAACCACCUCGAAGAGCUCCCAGAGAUUGUAGAAAGAGUCCAGUGUAACCAGCUUAGUAACCAGAGUAUCUGGAUUACCCAGGAAGGUUGAGCUGCUGAGAUUUCAGUGGUGCAAUGUCUUUAAAAAAACAGGCUUUGUUGGGAGGGUAUUUCCAUUUUGAACUUUGAGGACUGUUGGUCAGAAAAUGGGCUCAAAAGUGAGUUUGCUUAAUGAAGACAUUUAACGGUUGUGCUGUUUAUAGUAAAAUAAAACUCCCUACCUUGCUUCAGUUAAAAAUGAAGCACUUGGUUUCUUCCAUCCUCCUCCUCCCCUUAAUGGAUUGUGGCAGUUGAAAUAAUCCAUCGGAUGACCCACCUGUAGUGAGAUGUACUGUCGAUGUAGUGCCCGGUGUAUCUCAGUGGCCAUCUGCCAUGGUGAGGUGAGCGUGAUCUCUUUUCAGUAUAGUAGUUAACAUUUUCUAGUAUUUUUUAUGGAGAGAAUGUCAAAAGUGGCAUUUCAGACCCCGUCCCAGAUGGGUCUGAGGAAAGGAAGGCUGUAAAGGACAUGGUAAUGGCACUCCAUUCGGGAUGUAUUAAAAUAAUUUGCUUUUCAGGUAUUAAUAUGACAUUUGUCAUUGUCACUGAUUUUUUUAAAAAAGCAAUGCACAUGUUGGUUGUGGCUGUUUUCCGCAUGCUAUCUUCAUAUCUAAAUGCUUCAUUAAUUAUCCGAGCCUCCGGAGAAUUAACUCUAUUACGUUUGUAUAGUAAGUUUGUAAACUGCUUGGCAAACUGAUUAAGAAAUAAUUUGCAAUACCGUGCUACUAAAGUGGCAGGUUUCUGGUAGAAAUUGUGCGAGUCCAAUUUGGAGUUUUAAGUUCCUUGAUUGAUGAAACUAAAAAGGCAAUUUUGGAAAAAGAGAGGGGGAAAAGUAGAUCACUUAUCUUAGCAAACGGUUGAAAAUAUGUCUGUCCUCUGUGGCCCCAAAUCCAGUGAAAGAAAUUCUCCCAGUAAAAGUUGCUUCCUAACUCUGUUUUUCUCAGAAUACCUCUUACCUUUCUCAAAGAAAGCUUCAACCACCAUCAUCAGAAAGAAGGUGGCCUAAAAACUGACACAUGGCCAGUGCCCGGAGGGGUCUGGAGGCAUAAGUCUAGAUGCCCAGAGAGCAUCCAGGCACUGAACUGCUCAGAGCUUGAGAUGAAAUGACAUACAAGCUUCAGGGUAAAACUGUCUACUAGCAAGAUUACCUCCCUCAAUUCUACCAUUGCAGAUUUCUUCUGACCCCAAAUGCAACCUUACAGAGAAUGCUGAAUGAGGAAGGCCAAUUCCUUACAAUGAUGGCAGAACCCCCAAGCGAAUGCCCUAUUGAGGAGAAGGACAUCACUGUAUUUGGAAUUCUGCCUGCUAGUGAUAGCUCACACAUCACAUCCCAGAAUCCCACUCCCAAUGCAUUAUUUCCUGAGGCAAGAACUUAAGGUCCUCACCUAAUUCCUCCAUCACAACCAUUAACUCUUAUUGGACAAGCUCCUCCUGUGAGUAGGGCCUGUACUCACUUCCUCUUAGAUCAUAAUUCCAUCUUCAAGAGACUGAUUUCCAGAAUAGUAAUCUUUUUCCAGCGUUCUCUCUUCUCCAAUGCCCUGGUUGUUAUUUUUCCCACCUCUCCUAAUAUUGAUCUUCUUGUCUUUUGGUUAGAACUGCAACUUCGGAGUUGAGUUCAUUUCCUAUUGCUGCUCAAUUCAGUAGCAACAUAGCUGGCUUGUUCCCAGACCCAGGAAGUAUAAGUCAUUGACAGUUUCCUGAGUGGCUCUGCCAAUCCAUACCACCCUUGGUACUGUGAAAAGGCUUCUUGGCAGCCAGGUGGCAUUGAGGAUGGUAUUCAGGGCGCUUUCCUUCUGUCAUAUAGUUGUGGGAUCUCUACCAAGUGUGAAGGUGAAUGAGGUAAGGGAGAUCAGAACCAUGCUUCCUGGUUUUUCAUACAUCCAAGGAAGAAGUCCUGGUGUGGGUUGUUUGACACCUUCUUUCCACUUUCACCUUUUAUUUUUUAUUCCUUCCUUUCUACCCCCAACCAGUCGAGCAAAUGAGCAAUUUUGUGUUUCUAAUACAGGAUCUGGAAGUAGUGCUUUCUAAUCCUCAUUUCCUGUAGGAUGUUCCUGCACUAUAACAAGAUUAUGUUUUCUUCCUUCUGCAGCAGCUUUCUGCUUCUUGGGUACUACUAGCUAUUGUUCAAUUCAGGUGAGGCCUGUGAUGACAUAUAUGUAGCAUGUGCUCUGCGCUCCCUGCAAGCUGAGCAGAUACAACCAAUGCAUCACUGUAUACUCUUGCUGAGAAUGUGGAUGCAGCCUCACAGAUCUUUGCAACACUCCAACCAGCCAGGACCAGUUGAUCAGAACUGAUCUUAUUGGUCUGAUAACCAAUCUUAUUUGUGAACUGAUUCAUAUCUGUCUUUCCACUCUUGGUUCUCUUGCCGUAGAACAAAAACAGUUUAGGAAGCAUAAUUACGAACAUUUAGGAACCAAUAUGUAUAAGUAAUUCGGAGACUCCAAUUCACCUGCCCCUCCCCCAUCCCAGGUUGUGGAGGCUCGAGGAAGCUGACUUCUUAGGCUAAAGGACAAAAAAAUCUCUUUACCUCCUUGGCCAUUUUCAUGUUCUCUGCCAAUUACUAUAGGCAGUCUUCAUUUUGCAGAGGUGAGGUAAGACUUCAUCUUAUUCUUCAUGUAAUCCCACCUUCUAACAAAAAAUAAAUAAAUAUUUAAAUUCCAAGGAGAAGUGUUCUUUGUGUAUUUCUAGCAGAAAACAGAUGCUUAAGCCUAAGAAGGAAGAUCCGUCCAUGACAAAGGAAAGUGGAAAACUGAACCAGUUAUCUGAAUACUUCAUGCCAGGACAGUUGCUAUUAGCAACUGUUUUGCACCUUCAGGGCUUUAAAAUGGGCUCUGCAGACAGCAUUUGCAUAUGCAAGACUCAGUAGCCAAGCCUCCACUGCCAAUUGUUGAAGGCAGUUUCAGAUCGCCACCUUUUGAGGUACAUUUCUUUAAGCACAAGAGAAGUAGAAAUGGCCUUUGCCUUGUCUCCAGUGGUUUGUCCCUCUGGUGCCUCAGCAGAUACCAGAGCUUAUUCUUAUGACCAUUUGGAAGUAGUCCUCAAAGUAAAGAUCAAGAAAAAAUUGGAUUCUUUUUCCAUUUUCUCAUAAUAGUAGCCUAGUCAACACAAGACUCCCAUAAAAUAUGACUCACUAUUGGGAGCCAUACUAUUUUAUAAGCUUACUUCCUGCUGACAAAACUAGCUUUCCUCAAGGAAAUAUAAAGGAGGGGAAAGUCACAUAGUGUUAGGAAAACAUUCCUGUGUUUUGAAUACGAUGAAUCCAUAGGAUAGAGAAAAAUCUGCUUGUUCUAUUCUGAGAGUUCUCUGAGAUAUCCCUUCACUCUGCUUGGCAUUUGGCCAUUGAUAUUCAACAGGUCACUGACCAAGCUUUUCUAAAUUUUUCAGAGAGAGUUACUUACCAGUAAGGUCUGUUCUUAAACCUACCUAGUUGAUUUUCAUAUCUUUCCAUAAAGUGUCAUGAUUCUGUCAUAGACCCUGACUUAACAUUGUAAGGACUAUGAGUCCUCCAUUUUUUAAUUAAUUUUUUUUUAGCAAAUUAGGACUUCGGCAGGUUUUCCUCUCCUAAACUCAUUCUUUCCUCCACAGGAUUGCUUUGUCCAUCUCCUGCUUUCAUUUCAAGUGCAUAAACAAAACCUCAAAGGGCCUGGGAAGGUGAGGCAGGCCAGAGUCUGUGUUCUGUGUUGAGUGUCAAGCUAUUUGUUAAGAAGGUCUGCAACAGGCCUUUGGUGUGGGCUCUGCCAGAGACUGUUCUGAACACUUUGCUUGAGAUCCGUGCCCUGUAAAAUGGAUAUGAUGUUUUACUGAUGUCUGUAAUACAUUUGUAAACUUCCAAUAAAAUUUGAAUAAAAGAAAUGUUGCCAUUCUUCUCAGCCCUCCCUCACUUUCCAGAUUUUAGGGGUGGUCUCUGCCUUUGAGCAUUUCAACAAAGAAAAGAAAGGACACAGGUAUGGAGGGAUGAGUUUUACUAUGAAAUAUUAACCUGAUUGUUUAAAUCAGGGUUUCUAAGCCUCAGCAAUAUUGACGUCUUGUGCUAGUUAAUUCUCGGUUGCAGAGGGCUGUCCUGUGCAUUGUAGGAUGUUUAGCAACAUCGCUGACUUCUACUCACUAGAUGCCAGUAGCAGCCCCCAGAAACUGUGACAACUAAAAAUGUCUCCCAUCACAACCAUUAGGAUGGCAGUUAUUAAAAAUAACAACAAAUGUGGGUGAGGAUGUGGAGCAAUUGGAACACUUGUACACUGUUGGUGGGAAUGUAAAAUGAUGUAGUGCUGUGGAAAACAGUAUGGCAGUUCCUCAAAAAAAAUUAAAAAUAGAAUUACUACCAUAUGCUACUUCUGGGCUAUACCCAAAAGAAUUGACAGCAGGGUCUCCAAAGAGAUACUUGUACACCCAUAUUCAUAAAAGCAGCAUUCACAAUAUCCAAAAAGUGGGAGCAACCCAAAUGUCCACUGAUGGAUGAAUGUGUAAACAAGGUGUGGUGUAUACAUACAAUGGAAUAUUAUUCAGCCUUAAAACGGAAGGAAAUUCUGACACAUGCUACAACAUGGAUGAACCUUGAGGACAUUUUGCUAAGUGAGAUAAGCCAGUCACAAAAAGACAAGUGUAUGAUUCCAUUUAUCUGAGGCACCUAGAGUCAAAUUCAUAGAGACAGAAUGUAGAAGAGUGGUUGGUUGUCAGGGACUGAAGGGAGGAGGGAAUGGGGAGUUACUAUUUAAUGGGUAUAGAGUUUCAUUAUGGCAAGAUGAAAAGAGUUCUGGAGACGGGUUGCAGAACAAUGCAGAUGAACUUAAUACUACUGAACUGUACACUUAAAAGUGGUUAAGAUGGUAAAUUUUAUAUUAUGUUUAUUUAACCACAAUUAAAAAUGUCUCCACACAUUGUCAAUGUCUCCCUGUUGAGAACCACUGGUUUCAAUGCAUUGCCUUCUUAGUGUCUUUGUUCCUUGAGAAUUCUUGAAACUGAUUCCUACCCAGGCCACACAGUUAAUUUUCAGUUAUUAGCAAGAAUUGAAAGCAGCAGAUGACCCAAAAAUAUUUGUGUUUGCUUUUAAGCAAAUAAUAAGUGGUCUGUCUGGAGAAUUACAUCCAUGUCUGUGUUCUGGUUAGGGCAGCAUUAACACUGACUGGGAGCCAGGACCAAGGCAGCAUGUAAAUUCAAUUUCCCCGUGUCUGAUCCACAACAUUAGGGACUUGCUGGAUGCUAUAAUAUCAUCUAUUCAUUCAUUCAACAAAUAUUUAUCAAAAGGCUUUCUCUAGCCAGGAACCGUUCUAGGUGCUUGGAAUACAAUAAUGUGCAAAACAAACAAAAAUCCCUACCUUAAAGGAGUUUACAAACUUUACUUUCAACUAGGCAAGACAUUCGGAAUAGUAAGUAGUCUUACCCACCCUAGCUAAUCACAAGGACUUGGGAGUGGCAGACAACAAGAGUUGUUUCAUUGUAAGACAUUCUAAGAGCUUUUGAAUAAAAACUUGAACUGGAAAUGGCAA